AUGAGAGGGCUGGACCAGAUGGAAAUUCGGGGGGGGGGGGGGGGUCCGUAUCUCCUGCUGGGUGAGGUCGUUGGACACAGCGCACUUGGUGCGCAGCCCGCGCAGGCUGCCGAUGAGGUUCUGGAGCUGCCCGCACUGCUGCAGCGCCCGGCUGGCCGCCGCCCCUGCGCCUCCCACCGCGGCCGGCGCAUCACCCCCGCCACCGCCCUCCUUCUUCUCUCACAUCGCGGCCGCGCGGAGCGCCGCUCUAUGCAGGCCGCAGCGGCCAAGGCGGGGAGCCCGGGGCGCCGGCGCGUAGGCAAGGGACCCCCGAGCCGGGAGAGCUGGACCAGGAGCGCCCCUCAGCGCUGCCCGAGCCAGGACGCCGGUAGAGCUGGCAGCCGAGUGUGCCGCUCCCGCCCUCAGAGCCGCGGCGGGCAAAAAGCUGCGGCGUCGGGGGCAAAAAGGCGCGGCGUCGGGGGCAAAGAGCCGCGACGGCAAAAACCCGCGGCGGCGGGGGCAAAAAGCCGCGGGGGCAAAAGCCACAAAAAGCCGCGGCGGCGGGGGCAAAAAGCCGCGCCGGCAAAAAACAGCGGCGGCGGGGGCAACAAGCCGCAAAAAGCCGCGGCGGCGGGGGCAAAAAACCGCGGCGGCGGCGGGGGCAAAAAACCGCGG